AGUCCUGGGUUGUACCCGGCGCAGCUGGGAGCGGCUGCUUCCUCCGGGGUCGUAUCUCCGCCCGGCAUGGGGCUGCUGGACCUUUGCGAGGAAGUGUUCGGCACCGCCGACCUUUACCGGGUGCUGGGCGUGCGACGCGAGGCCUCCGACGGCGAGGUCCGACGAGGCUACCACAAGGUGUCCCUGCAGGUACACCCGGACCGGGUGGGUGAGGGCGACAAGGAGGACGCCACCCGCCGCUUCCAGAUCCUGGGAAAAGUCUAUUCCGUUCUCAGUGACAGAGAACAGAGAGCAGUGUACGAUGAGCAGGGAACAGUGGACGAGGACUCUCCUGUGCUCACCCAAGACCGAGACUGGGAGGCGUAUUGGCGGCUACUCUUUAAAAAGAUAUCUUUAGAGGACAUUCAAGCUUUUGAAAAGACAUACAAAGGUUCGGAAGAAGAGCUGGCUGAUAUUAAGCAGGCCUAUCUGGACUUCAAGGGUGACAUGGAUCAGAUCAUGGAGUCUGUGCUUUGCGUGCAGUACACAGAGGAACCCAGGAUAAGGAAUAUCAUUCAGCAAGCUAUUGACGCCGGAGAGGUCCCAUCCUAUAAUGCCUUUGUCAAAGAAUCGAAACAAAAGAUGAAUGCAAGGAAAAGGAGGGCUCAGGAAGAGGCCAAAGAAGCAGAAAUGAGCAGAAAGGAGUUGGGGCUUGAUGAAGGCGUGGAUAGCCUGAAGGCAGCCAUUCAGAGCUGCAGGAGAAUAUCUGGCAAGGUGCAUUUAAUAUUUGGAAAAAAGAUAUGACCAGUAACCUACUUUAGGAAGAAAAUAAGCAUCACCUGGCAUCAGGUAGGCAUCGUAAGGUUGAGCUGUCCUAUCUGAAAAAAUAUGCGAUAUAAUUUAUUACAGAAGUUACUUUAUACUAAUGCUUAACAUUUAUGUUUUUAGUUACACACCCCUUCCAUUUUAAUCUGCUGAUAGGGUAGGACAUCUAAAGAGAGUUUUAGGAAUGACAUCUAUUUGAUGAGGUCAGAUUUUCAACAGCAAAAUGACUUAAAACUGAGUACAACUCUCCAGAAAUGAACACAGGCUGAAGUAUUCUGAAGCCAGUGAUAUUGUCACUGAUGAUUUGCUGCUUUUUGUGUAUGUGUGAGCUCAUCAAAUCCUAUAUGAUUGAACUGAUCAUUGUUAAGAGAUAACAUGAGCAGUGAUUUGGGUAUUAUUCACUGUUGCAUCUUUGGGUACAAACUUGCCUUUCCAAUGGGAUAGGUUAAUUUCUGCUGAAAGAGACAGUAACUGGAGAUAGAAACAACACUCAUGUCAUUUUUGGCUGCUAUGGUGUUUUGUUCUUCGGUCACUUGUGCCAAAAUCACUCUUCAUGAAGAUGAUUUCUAGUCGAUCUUCUAUACAAGCUCUGCAUCACUUGAUGACUGAAUACUGCUUCAUGAAAUCUCGUGUUUCCUGCAGCCUGAUAGAUUCUUCUCAUUUGCCUUAUGGUCCCUGCCUGGUUCGAGAGACUGGUCUGCCUCCGCUUUGAGAUUUUGUAGACCCAUGUAACUGAGGACCUGUCAGAUGACAUAGAGUAACAUUAGUAGACAGUCUAGGUUUGAUAAUCACUCUCAAGUUUAUAGCUAAGGGCUUUUUUGCUCCAAUUAUGAAUUGGACUUUCUUAAGGUAUGAAAGCAGUAAACUAGUUUUGUAGAAGAGCCCACUAAUUAAAAAGAAGCAAGAUGUCUGAUUUACUCACUUCCACUUCAGUGUUACAUAAGUUAUACCUGAGGUUUUUUUUUUUUUUUGGAGGUGGAGUCUCACUCUGUCCCCCCAGGCUGGAGGUGCAGUGGCAUGAUCUCGGCUCACUGCAAGCUCUGCCUCCCAGGUUCACCUCAUUCUCCUGCCUCAGUCCCCCGAGUAGCUGGGACUACAGGCAUCUGCCACCACACCCGGCUAAUUUUUUGUAUUUUUAGUAGAGAUGGGGUUUCACCAUGUUAGCCAGGAUGGUCUCAAUAUGCUGACCUCGUGAUCCGCCCGCCUUGGCCUCCGAAAGUGCUGGGAUUACAGGCAUGAGCCACCACGCCCAGCCAGUUAUACCUGACUUUCAAUGUGGCUGAAAUUGUAGCUCAAAUGCAGAUCUGAAAGCAUAAUCUGACAAAAGCAUUCAAAGACUACCAGACAAUGCUGCGGGGAACUGAGCUGAGAAAUCACUUGGACUACAAAGAUGGUUUGAGGCAGACUAGUUUUUUACCAUAGUUGCUGAUUAUUUUGAUCAUUAACAGGAAACAUCUCAGCUGUCCAUUACUUCUAAAUUUACCUUCAGCAUAAUAAGAAUGACCCUGAUGGUGGUGAGAAGACUGUCACAGGAAGAAUUAAGACAUCCUGCAGCCUGGGCAACAUAGCAAGACCCUGUCUCUACAAAAAAUAAAUUACCUGGGCAUGGUGGCACUGCUUGUAGCCCUAGCUAUGUGGGAGGCUUAGGUGGGAGGAUCCCUUGAGCCCCGGAGUUCGAGGCUACAGUGAGCCAUGAUCAUGCCACUGCAUUCUGGCCUGAUCAGCAGAGUGAGACUGUCUCAAAAAAGACAUCCCUCAAUUUUCUCCCAUCACUUCUUUGUUAGUACAUCUACAGAGUAUAAUUUAAAGAUAAAAAGAGUUAAUGCGAUAGAAUCAGACUCAGCAUAUCCUGAUGGUUUAGAAUUUCUUUUCUUACCUUGGCCUAACAGAUUAACUGAUCAAAGCAGUUUAAUCCAUAGGAAUAUGGAUUUUGCCUGCAUAAUAAAAUCCAUGCUAUGUUCUUAAAGAAUAUUUUGAACAUUACAACAAGGACUAAUUUGGGUUGAACUUUUUAGAUUUAAAAAAAAAAAAAAGGCAGUUUACCAAAGUAGUGAGAAGUUAAUUUACAUGGUAUGAAGAAAAUAGGAAUCUGAAACUUUUUGGCUCUGAGCAAUAGAACUCUCCUAGCUUUUUAUUAUACCCCAUGUUCCAAAAUGAAUUUUAGGUGAUUUACAAAGAUGUGGGAAAACAUUAAAUCCAAGAAAAUCUGAAAGAAGGGGAAAUAGGUGUAGGAAAAAAGACAAAGGCUGGGUCUUAACACAACCACACAGUAGUAAAUAAGGGCCAUGGCCCCACCUUUACCUGCAGAUCCCCUGCCAGGUCGGGCCUGAUGAGGAUACUCAACUGCACAUGAGCGACGAUACUGUGUAUCCAGCUACAAGACAAAAGAGGAGACACUUCUUAUGAUGCAUCUUCUCACAAAGGAUAAUAUUUUAGCAGGUUCACAGGAACACCUUGAAAUCAACAGUGGUAAAAGGCAUAGACUACCAACUUGAGGGAAAAGUCAGCUGAGUGCACUGGGUUGAAUUUCAAGUAGAAAAUCCCAAGCCAGAUGCCCACAAAGCCAUUUAUUGUAAAAAUUGCAGAUUCUUCAAUAUUAUUACUAUGCCGUUAAGGAAAUCAGGAGUUAUAAAUAAUCCAUAUGGUUUAAUAUUUCAGUUAGUUCUAAGGGGGUUCGUCUCAUUUCUUUUUGUUGGCUGCUGCAUAUAUUUUAAAUGAAUGCUUUCAUUUAAAACAACCAGCCUUUUCAGCAACAUUGAAAUACUUAUGACUUUACCACCAUAUCGAAAUUUAACUUUACAUUUACUUUUUAGCAUUAUGAAAUGCAAAUAUUUCACAGUUACCUCAAGGAAUUAAAAAAUGUAGAGAUACGACUACAAUAUUAAAAUGCAAAUAUCAAAUAAAGCUAUAUAUGACAUCCUGCUGGGGCUUCUGGAAUAAAAACAUCCCCCAGUAGUUCCCUUGAGAGAGCACUGAAAUCAAGAGAUUUCAGGAAGCUUUUUCUGGUGAAGCCCCUAUAUUUUAGAGAUCAGGGGUCAGCAAACUUAUUUUUUGCAAAGGGCCAGAUAGUUAUUAUAUUAGGCUUUGUGGACCAUAGGGUGGUUGUUGCAAUUACUCAGCUUCGCUGUUAUGGUAUGAAGGCAGCCAUAGAUAGCACAUAAAUGAGCUUGGUGGCACUGCUCCAAUAAAAGUUUAUUUACAAAACAAGGCGGUAGGCCAAGUGAGUAGCCCAGGAACUGUAGUUUACUGGCCCCUAUUCUAGAUGAAAACAGCAAGGAGCAAAGUGCUAGUCUGUAGUGCCAGGCCCAGGACAGCUAGCAUUCUUUUUUUUGUGGGGGGACAGAGUCUUCUCGCUCUGUCGCCCAGGUUGGAGUGCAAUGGCACGAUCUCGGCUCACUGCAACCUCUGCCUCCUGGGCUCAAGCAAUUCUCCUGCCUUAGCCUCCCGAGUAGCUGGGAUUACAGGCAUGCACCACCAUGCCUGGCUAAUUUUCUUGUAUUUUUAAUAGAAACGGGUUUCACCAUGUUAACCAGGCUGGUCUCAAACUCCUGACUUCAGGUGAUCUGCCCACCUCAGCCUCCCAAAAUGCUGGGAUUACAGGUGUAAGCCACUGCAGCCGGCUCACAGCUAGCAUUCCUAAUAAACUAAACAACUAGCUAUCUCCCUUUUUAUGACAGCAAAUGGGGAGAGAAAUGGUAAGUAAUUUUUACUUUUUUUUUAAUAAACUUAAAGAGAAGACUGAAACAUUUUCAUCUGUUCAGUUUUAUUCCUAAGGCAAUCAAAAAUUAAAUGUUUUUAGCCAGGUGCAGAGGUGCACACCUGUAAUCCCAGCUACUUGGGAGGCUGCGGUGGGAGGAUCACUUGAGCCCAGGAGUUUGAGGCUGCAGUGUGCUGAUUGCACCACUACACUCCAGCCUGGGUGAUGUAGCGAGAUACUUUGUCUCUUAAAAAAAAUGAAAUGUUUGGCUGAGAGCGGUGGCUCACGCCUGUAAUCCCAGCACUUUGGGAGGCCAAGGUAGGUGGAUCACUUGGGGUCAGAAGUUCAAGACCAGCCUGGGCAACUUGGAGAAACACUGUCUUUACUAAAAGAAUACAAAAAUUAGCUGGGCAUGGUGGCAGGUGCCUGUAGUCCCAGCUACUCAGGAGGCUGAGGCAGGAGAAUCGAUUGAACCCAGGAGGAGGUGGAGGCUGCAGUGAGCUGAGAUUGCACCACAGCACUCUAGCCUGGGCGACAGAGUAAGACUCCGUCUCAAAAAAAAAAAAAGUUUCAGAGAAUCUAGCUGUGUAAUAUAAUCAUCAAGUACUACUUAAUAAAUGUCCUGUGUCAGAUUAUAAGAAGGCAAAUUCAGUAGAAGUUCUCAAACUUUCUGGGGUUCACACUGAACCCCAAGAAUCAGAAAUGCUCAUGUUUCCUUUUCUUGUUUUUGGUGAGUUUCUCCCUAAGUCAGCCUCGUGGGGUCUACUAGAAUGAACAGUGUUCCCUCAAAAUUUAUGUCCACCUGGAACUUGUGAAUGUGACCAAGUUUGGAAAUAGGGUCUUUGCAGAUAAAUCAAGUUAAGGUAAAGUCGCACUAGAUUAGGGUGGGCCCUAAAUUCAGCGACUGGUAUCUUAUAAGAAGAGGGAACCCUGGACACAGACACACAGGGAGGAAAGCCAUGUAAAGACAGAGGCAGGCUGGGCAUGUGGCUCAUGCCUGUAGUCCCAGCACUUUGGGAGGCUGAGGUGGGAGGAUCACUUGAACCUCGGAGUUUGAGACCAGUCUGGCCAACAUAGUGACACCCUAUCUCUACAAAAUAAAAAAAUUAGCAGGGCAUGGUGGCAUGUGCCUGUAGUCCCAGCUACUCAGGAGGCUGAGGUGAGAUGAUCACUUAAGCCCAGGAGGUUGAGGCUGCAGUGAGCUGUGCUCUGCACUCCAGCCUGGGCAACAGAGUGAGACCCUGUCUUAAAAAAAAAAAAAAAGAAAAGAAAAAAAAGGCCGGGUACAGUGGCUCACACCUAUAAUCACAGCACUUUGGGAGGCUGAGGUGGGCAGAUAAUGAGGUCAGGAGUUCGAGACCAGCCUGGCCAAGAUGGCAAAACCCCAUCUCUAGUAAAAUUACAAAAAUUAGCUGGGCGUGGUGGCAGGCACCUGUAGUCCCAGCUAUUCGGGAGGCUGAGGCAGGAGAAUCACAUGAACCCAGUAGGCAGAGGUUGCAGUGAGCUGAGAUUGCGCCAUUACACUCCACCCUAGGUGACAGAGCGAGACUCCGUCUCAAAAAAAAAAAAAAAAAAGGCAGAAAUUGGGAGUGAUGCAGCUGCAAGCCAAGGAACACCAGGGAUCACAGGUGGCCACCAGAAUCCAGGAAGAGACAAAAAGAUUCUUCCCUAGACCUUGCAAAGGGAGCAUAGCUCUGUUGACACCUUGAUUUUGAACUUCUCGCCUCUGGAACUGUGAGGAAAAAAUUUCUGCUGUUUUAAGGCACCCAGUUGUUUGGUCAUUUCUUAAGCCCUAGGAAACUAAUACAGAGGUCUGAUAUUGAUUAUCCUUACCACUCUUCUCAUAGAAGAAAAACUUUGCAGUGCUUUAGCCUGCUGUGGUUCAAGGGUCAUGAGUUGGGACAAGUGUGCUGCAAACACUACCAUCCUGAAAACUGUCAGGAUGUGGGGUCCCUGGUUACUUCCCCAGGCUCUCCAAGUGCUCUUGCCACAAAGCAGAUUAUGUGGGGUCGAGCUCCCAGCCUACAAAUGGGGAGGGUCAGUGCAUGACCCCAUUGCUGAUCAGGUUUUUUCUAUUACUUAAAAGGGCUAGUAAAUGCCUAAUAAAUGGUAGGCAGUGUCAGCAUUUAAAACACCAGUAGAAAGAAAAAGUCCUAAGCUGGGUACAGUGGUGUGCACCUGUAGUCCCAGCUACUCGGGAGGCUAAGGCAGGAUUGCUUGAGCCCAGGAGUUCCAGGUCUAGUCUGGGCAACAUGGCAAGAGCCUGCUUCUGAAAAAAAUUUUUUAUUAAAGUCCCAACUCACUCAUCCACCAGGACUCAUCAUAAUCUGAGACCACUUUUGAUGUAAUUCCAGAAGAACAGGAUUACAUAAUAAAGUUAUGCUUAUCUGAUGUGUACUGGGAUUUAAUAUUCUUGCUUGUGGUCAGACAUAUCUUAAGUGUUAAAUUGCUUAGAAUAUUUGUGAUUUCUGUAUAAGGCAUUAAAGAAUAGGCAUCAGGGACUAGUUAGAAUUUGAACAAAAUGUAUUUAUAACACUUUUUAUUGUUGGAAACUCAACUUUUAUUCUGGGUUAAGCCUCUAGAUAAAAUCUUAAGUCUGCCAAACUAUUAUUCCCCCCACCUUUUCUUUCCCCAACUAUCAAGACCAUUCUAGGAAGUACGUCACUCUACCAAAAAUGAUUGAGUUGUGUUGGGCCUGGGGAAAAAGUCGGGCAAAAGGAGCCUUUCUUGUGGCUGCUGAUAGUUAGGUUCAUCCACCACCGCACUUUGAGCUCGACUAGAGUCGCCAUGGGGUUUCUGCAGAGGAGACAAAAGUUACAGAAACAGUGAAAACUAUCUGUAAUGUGGUAUGUAGUUAAAACCCUAUCGACCAUGGCAGAUAUGGUAAGUGCAGGCCAAACAGCUCCAAUUCCACGUCAUAAAUUAGCACUGUGUUUGUACUUUUGACAAAACACAGUAUAAAUCAAGAUCAGGGCACAGAUCCUGCAGAAUUACUGCCCAUUAGGUUGUAUGGUAAGUACAUGGAGAGGCAAUAUGAAAGAAACAUACCAUCUGUCUUUGUGGCCCCACAGUGCUCACAUGUUCCACUUCAGCUGUGCCAAUAGGUGGUAGCAGAUUAUUUCGACUCAGGGGCGUCGGUGAGGGAGAGGAGAGCGAGUCGGGUGCCACUGGGCUGCAGAUCCCACCAACAAACACGAAGGUAUGAAAGCAUGAAGUUAUAACAAUACCAGCAAAUUGAUUAGAAAUCAGAUAAAUGAAGCAGAUGAGUUUAAUGUGCACAGAAAGCUUUAGGCUACCUAUGUUUUCAAGUAGAGAUCUCAGGAUUUUUGGAAAAUUAGUUUUUAAAAUAGUGUUUUCUGAUUUUGUUUUGAAGCUCUAUACUCUGGGUACACAACAGAAGCUGGCCUUUUCUCUCCCACAGAACUGGAAUAAAACAUUUGUCCCUA